GUCCGAGGAGAGCCAGGCCAUGCAGGCCCACGUGGUAGGUGCCAGCGGGGAGGGUGCCCCGCCGUGCAGGCUGGGUCCUCGCGUCCCCUCACCCCGCCCUCCAGUCCUCUCUCGCUCCGGGGUUCGCAGCCCCGCACCGCCUCUCGGGCUCACCUACGGGGUCUCCGCCCUGAGCAGCCCUUAGGCCCCGCGGGCGAGCGCGGCUGCGCGUGCGGGGGACGCUCGGGAUUGGAGCCCGCGGGGCGCGGCCGAGAUCUGCAGCUCCGGCUGCGCUUCCUGCCCCCGUCCCGCGAGCGUGGCCUCCUCACCGACCUUCCUCGUUCUGAUUUUGAAGCUUCCGGGCUCGGAGCUCAGGCAGUUCCCCGUUCGCCCUCACCUGGUCGUGGGGUGGAGGAACGGCGCACCUGCCUCAUCCCCGCCCGCCUGCCCCGCGCUCCUUCCCCGCGCCCGCACACCUGCCUCGCUCCCGCCUCGCUCCUGCGCACCUGCCCCGCCCCCGCGCACCUGCCCCCGCACCUCACACACCUGGUCCGCGCACCUGCGCAUCUGCCUCGCUCUUACGCACCUGCCUUGCCCCUGCACGCCUGCCCUGCACACCUGCCCCGCCCCCGCACACCUGCCCCACACCCCACACACGUGCCCCGCGCUCCUGACUCGCCCCCGCGCACCUGCCGCGCGCACCUGCCUCGCUCCCGCACCCCACACACCUGGUCUGCACACCUCCCCGUGCCCCACACCUGCCUGCACACCUGUCCGUGUGCCCCCACACAACCUCGCACCCCACACGUCUGCCGUCACACAUUCCCGGCACACUUGCCCAUGCCCCACACACACGUCUUGUGCCUGCACACCUGCUUCACACACCUGCUCUGCGUCCUGCAUACAUGCCCGUGCCCCAUACCUGCCCGUGCACCUGCCGUGCACACCUGCCUGCGCAUCCCACACACCUACCUGCACACCUCCUCCGUGCCCACACACCUGCCUGUGUGCCCAGCACACUUACCCCAAACACGUGCCCUAAAAACCUGCCCUUAAGCCCCGAACACCUUCCCCGUGCUCCGGCAGAGGCUGGAGCAAAGGCCCUCAGGGUUCAGACCCAGCCAAUAGGCCGAUGCAGGGAACAACCACAGGGAUGUAGGAUUAGCAGUCGCCCAAAGGCUCAGCAUGUUUUCUGUUUUUUGUUUUUUUGUUUGUUUUUUUUCCAGCCUUUUUUCUUUUUUAUUCCAGUCUUACUAAAAUUGGUAACAGGUGAAUCAAGGUCUAUCUUUGAUAGAAACAUUAUAUUUUGUAGAUCUUGAGAAAAAUUAUUUCCUUCUUUUCCUCUAAGUAAAUCCAAACUAAGGCUGGAGUACAAUGGCGCGAGCUCGGCUCACCGCAACCUCUGCCUCCCGGGUUCAAGCGUUUCUCCUGCCUCAGCCUCCCGAGUAGCUGGGAUUACAGGCAUGCACCACCACACCAGGUCUAUUAUCCUCCCAGUCCACAACGCUGAACCGUGGCUGGACGAAUGUUUGAGGUCUGUUUUGCAACAGGACUUUGAAGGUACCAUGGAGCUGUCUGUUUUCAAUGAUGCCAGUAAGGACAAGUCUGGGGCUAUCAUUGAAAAAUGGAGAGUGAAGCUGGAAGAUUCUGGUGUCCACGUGAUCAUUGGGGGGCACGAUUCUCCCUCUCCUAGAGGCGUCGGAUACGCUAAAAAUCAAGCAGUUGCCCAGAGCUCAGGGUCUUACCUUUGCUUUUUGGAUUCGGAUGACGUCAUGAUGCCCCAGCGGGUGAGGCUGCAACACGAGGCUGCCGUUCAGCACCCGUCGAGCAUCAUUGGUUGCAGAGUGAGGAGAGAUCCCCCUAACUCCACCGAACGAUACACACGUUGGAUCAACCAGCUGACGCCGGAGCAGCUCCUAACCCAGGUUUUCACCUCAAAUGGCCCCACGGUGAUCAUGCCCACCUGGUUCUGCUCGCGAGCGUGGUUCUCCCACGUGGGCCCCUUUAACGAGGGAGGUCAGGGCGUCCCGGAGGACCUGCUGUUCUUCUACGAGCACCUCAGGAAGGGCGGCGGCGUCAUCCGCGUGGACCAGAGUCUCCUGCUGUAUCGCCACCACCCACAGGCGGCCACGCACUGCGUCCUCGAGACGACCAUCUGGACCCACCGCGUCCGCUUCCUGGAAGAGCAGGCCCUGCCCCGCUGGGCGGCCUUCACCAUCUGGAACGCUGGCAAGCAGGGGCGCCGGCUGUACCGCAGCUUGACUGCCGGCAGCCAGCGCAAGGUGGUGGCAUUCUGUGACGUGGACGAGAACAAGAUCAGGAAAGGCUUCUAUUGCCACGAGGACUCUCAGGAAAGACCCAAGCCCCGAAUCCCCAUCCUGCACUUCCGAGCCGCCCGGCCACCCUUCGUCAUCUGCGUGAAGCUGGACCUCACAGGGGGCGCCUUUGAGGACAACCUGAGGUCACUGCACUUGCAGGAGGGCCAGGACUUCCUUCACUUCAGCUGACGGACCCAUGGCAGCUGCUCCCAGUGCAUCCCAGGCCAGCAGGAGCUUUGUGAGCUGCAGGCAUGGCGAUGGUGCGCCUGUUCCACACCCAGCAGGCGCAACCAGAGUCUCGUGUGUGCCGACCACAGGAGCCAAGCCUUUUCCACUGUGUGGACUCAUGUGGCCAAGGCUAGGCCUGGUCACCCAGGACCCUCACCACGUGACCCCAGCCAAUCGGGACAGUUCAAGGAGGAGGAGACCCCUAUUACACAGGUUGGAAUAAAAUAUUUAAAUCUCGUAAAAAUGUAACCCAAGGCUCUUUUAGGGUAUAAAGACCAUUGGCCACCAGGUCAAACACAACAACAGUAGUGUGUUAACCCCACACUCCUGUGUGGCCAGGUCGUCACACACAUCCCGUGAAGAGCUGUCUGCUAAACACACAGCACGGACUGUCACAGUCCUGGUCUUGUGGUCCUGGUGACCUCACAAGCCUCACAGAUGCGGUGGCACCUCCCAGUUCUCGGCCUGCCCAUGUUCCUGUGUCCAGGCCCCAUCCCCACCUGAGAGCAGGCCAGGGAGCCACCCUAAUCUACACCACGCACAUGGCACCCCUGGGCUCCUCACAUAGGGAAAGGGUUGCUCACCCAAGCCCUUGGGCCUCUGAGUGGCCACACCUGGGGCUGCUUUGGUGCUGCUGGCCGUGGUUCUGCACCUCAAGCCCUAUGAGCACAGCACAGGUCCCAGAGAUGGGUGUGGGUUGCUACCACAGUGAAAUUUUUAUACACGUUCCCCUCACCAGCUUUGGGAUGGAUCAGCACGAGCUCAGACACAGAGACAAAGGUAGCCUCCUGCCCUUUGCCUAAAAACCCAAGUGUGGACUCUGCCCAGGCUCUCCUAAGACAGUGUAAUUAUUUCAAGAAUGGUAUUUAUUUCCGACAUUACUGUAGAGGCACACAUUGGACUCUGACGAUUCCCCUUGCAGCAGACAUUUGUGAAGCUGCUGGUCGGCACACCCAUCAAUCAGUGACUCCUGCACUGCAGAGGGGCCACAUGCACGAUGCUCACGUGUGCACAGGGGGGAGGACAGCACCCCCACCAGGCAGACGGGCCCAGAAACAGCAUCUGCCCAGCACUCCAGACCAUGCCUGCCACCAGGGCUUCUCAGUUCUCUAGCAUUUGAACCUCUGAUUUAACAUUCAUCUCUCUCCAAGACUGGGUGGGGCACUGCCUGUGGCCAGACGUCUCCCACAGCAGGGACAGCACCAGGCAAGAAGGGGGCCUGGUCUCCAGGCAGGAGGAGUGCAGCCCACCUCCCCUCUGGCUGACCCCUGGGCAGUGAGCCUUUCCAUCACCCCUACACACAUCAGGCUCAGAGACAAAAGGCAGGAACUUCUUGGUACAUGAUUUUAUAGGAAGCACAUUUGUGUUCAAGUGAAGGCAGAGGCGUCCACCCCAAGUCACCAGAGCGCAGGUGCAGAGAGGAAAAGCUGUCAGCUAGUGCCAGCCUCCAAGGGCCAGCGCUACCCUUCAACAGCUGGAGGCACCACUGUGCGAGGCUUUCCACACCGGCCUCCCUCAGGAACAAGACAUCCUCACCAGGCAGGGGUGAGGUAUGGGCUCCAGGACUGGCUUCAGCAGGCACCAGGCUGAAGAAGAGACAAGACAAGCUCAGGCUGGUCAGCUCCAACACACACCAUUCCCAGCCAGGGGACCCUCACCCCUCUGGGCCCUGUGUGGGGACUGACACGGUUCCUGCAGGAAACCAUUUGUGCCGUUUCCCACACACCCGGCAGCCUGAGCUAUGUGGCUGACAGGUGCUCAUGACUAACGUGUCCUCGGAAGGGCACCCCAUCUGGGGAGCGGGAAGGGAGGUUCACUGCACUGCUCUUAACCUGCAUUCACACGUUUGAAAUUUUUCCUAAUAAAAAUGUAAAAAGCACAUUUAA